AUCAUUCCUUCCCAAAGCCACCGGAAGCAUUCCUUCUAGGAAAGGUGGAGUCGGUAGUGAGAAGCCGGAGGUGAGAAGACCCCUGAGCGGAUGGAUUCAUUCAUUUUCUGAAUUUCCUAUGUGAGGACAGUAUUAGAGCCCAGUGAGGCUUUGAGAGGCCCCAAAGAUGAGCGCCAACAGCAGCAGAGUGGGCCAGCUUCUCUUGCAGGGUUCAGCGUGCAUUAGGUGGAAGCAGGAUGUGGAAGGGGCUGUCUACCACCUAGCCAACUGCCUCUUACUCCUGGGCUUCAUGGGGGGCAGUGGGGUGUAUGGAUGCUUCUAUCUUUUUGGCUUCCUGAGUGCAGGUUACCUGUGCUGCGUGCUGUGGGGCUGGUUCAGUGCCUGUGGCCUGGACAUUGUUCUUUGGAGCUUCCUGCUGGCUGUGGUCUGCCUGCUCCAGCUGGCACACCUGGUAUACCGCCUGCGUGAGGACACCCUCCCUGAGGAGUUUGACCUCCUCUACAAGACGCUGUGCCUGCCCUUGCAGGUGCCCCUACAGACAUACAAGGAGAUUGUUCACUGCUGCGAGGAGCAGGUCUUAACUCUGGCCACUGAACAGACCUAUGCUGUGGAGGGUGAGACACCCAUCAACCGCCUGUCCCUGCUGCUCUCUGGCCGGGUUCGUGUGAGCCAGGAUGGGCAGUUUCUGCACUACAUCUUUCCAUACCAGUUCAUGGACUCUCCUGAGUGGGAAUCACUACAGCCUUCUGAGGAGGGGGUGUUCCAGGUCACUCUGACUGCUGAGACCUCAUGUAGCUACAUUUCCUGGCCCCGGAAAAGUCUCCAUCUUCUUCUGACCAAAGAGCGAUACAUCUCCUGCCUCUUCUCGGCUCUGCUGGGAUAUGACAUCUCAGAGAAGCUCUACACUCUCAAUGACAAGCUCUUUGCUAAGUUUGGGCUGCGCUUUGACAUCCGCCUUCCCAGCCUCUACCAUGUCCUGGGUCCCACUGCUGCAGAUGCUGGACCAGAGUCCGAGAAGGGUGAUGAGGAAGUCUGUGAGCCAGCUGUGUCCCCUCCUCAGGCCACACCCACCUCUCUCCAGCAAACACCCCCUUGUUCUACCCCUCCAGCUACCACCAACUUUCCUGCACCUCCUACCCGGGCCAGGUUGUCCAGGCCAGACAGUGGCAUACUGGGUGAGGACUCCACCAGUCUGGUGCUGGAGGAUUUUGAGGAGGUGUCAGGAUCAGAAUCGUUUAUGGAUUAUAGGAGUGAUGGGGAGUACAUGAGGUGAAGGGAGAACUAACAUGGGCACAGCCACCGGCUCAGGAUCCUAUCUUCUAGAAUUCCUCUCCAGAGCUACUCUCAAGUUAUAUCCAGGGGACAGGCCCCUUUGGCUCCAACCCACACGCCUGAACUUUAAGGAUCAUUGGACUAUCUUCUCUGUGGCCAGCGCAGCUCUCUUCUGUGUUCACAGAAUGGCCACUGAUAGGCAUGCCUCUUUUCCCACCCACUGGAAGGCUCACAGGCAAGGUGAGAGAGGACACAGAAGGUGCCAACACUGUCGCUACAGUAAGGACCUGAAGUGACUUUGAGAAAUUCACCCUCACAAACCUUCCUUCAGGAGCAGGCAUUGGUAGUGCAGAGGCACAGAUUCCGUCCUUUACCAGCUGCAGAAUCUUGGGCAAGUUACAUAGCCUCUGUGAGCCUCAUCGGUAAACAGUGGGGGUUAUGAAACCCACCUCACAGGGUUGUUGUGAGGAUCCAAUGAGUUGAUUUAGGUAAGCACCUAGCACAUGCCGUGGCACCAAGUAAGCACUCAAUAAAUCACUCAACUCCUUUC